GUCACCAUGGCUGACCGGGCUGCUGCCGAAAGGGCCUGCAAGGAUCCCAAUCCCAUCAUUGAUGGCAGAAAGGCCAACGUGAACCUGGCAUACUUAGGAGCAAAACCAAGGAUCAUGCAACCAGGUUUUGCCUUUGGUGUUCAACAACUUCAUCCAGCCCUUAUACAAAGACCUUUCGGGAUAAACAUUUUCACUUAACACCUUAAUUCAGAGAUACCAACCUAGCACCCACAGUGUUGUUCUUGGAACUUUGAGAGUACAAGGGGUUAAGGUUUCGGUGUCAGUGAGAUCCGCACUGGCUGGCCUUUGCAGCUGAUAGAUGUUUUACUUUGGCCUUAUAAAGACAUUUUACCCGCUGGAAACCCUUGUCGCAUGACAGGAUCAAAAAUAGCCCGGCUGCAGCCCCUGCUGUCCAUCACCACAUGUAAACUGGCAUAAGAGUAGGCUCUCUUAGCCGUGUCUACACGUUGUAGACACGGCAGCCUCCAGGGACAGUGUUUCAUAAAGCCACACCUGUUGUUGCGAGUGAGCCAGUCACCUGACCUGCAGCAAAGUUCUGAGUGUGUGCAUGACCACGCGCCUGGUUUCUGACAAGCAGUUAAGAACAUCUCUGAGUGUCCUCAGAAACACUUGAUGACGUCGUUUCUCCUGGCACUGGGAAACAUCUACAAGUCUGAGAUAAACAAGCUGGCUGACCCUCAGGUGCCUGAUAGUCAAACAGGAUACCUGCCCACUAUGUCUAUCCGCAGGCUUUUGUGCAGCCGGGAGUGGUCAUUCCACACGUCCAGCCGACAGCAGCUGCCGCCUCCACCACCCCUUACAUUGAUUACACUGGAGCUGCAUACGCACAAUACUCAGCAGCUGCUGCUGCUGCCGCCGCCGCUGCUGCCUAUGACCAGUACCCCUAUGCAGCCUCUCCAGCUGCUGCAGGAUAUGUUACUGCUGGGGGCUAUGGCUACGCAGUCCAGCAGCCAAUCACCGCAGCGGCACCUGGGACAGCUGCCGCCGCCGCUGCAGCAGCUGCUGCCGCUGCAGCAUUUGGCCAGUACCAGCCUCAGCAGCUGCAGACAGACCGAAUGCAAUAGACCAGCCAUCUGAUCAAAGUUGAAUUGUUUUCUCUUUCCCUCCCAAUUUUCCAAUUUUUAGUAGCUAAUAAGAGAGUUAACAUUGACUUAACAGCUUUAAAAAAAAAAACAGCCAUGCUAUUGUGAAGCAGAGUUAUUAUUUUUUUUAUACUCCAGGUAGUGUUCUAGAUGAGAAAGAGGUAAGAAUGAGGGGAAUGGGCACAAUUUUGGAAAUCAAUCCCAAAGAGCCUGAGUAAAUGAAAGGCCACUACGAAAUGACGCCAGGAGUAACAACGGAACUUCACUUUUGUAACGGGAUUUUUAUUUUUGCUCUUUUUAUAGUAUCAGGGAAGCAAACUGCCUUUUACAAGUUAGAAAAUGCUGUUUGAAUCUAGUUGAACCAGGGAAUACAGAGCGAGCAAUAUGUAGCUUGAAUUACAUUUAAAAGCAGAUUUUUUACAAACAAAAUGGCGAAAGCACUGAUUGUCAUUUUUAGCAGUCACUUAAGGCCUAUAGAACUUUUUUCAAGUCGGAAGGUCCUGUUCUUACUAUCUCAAAAAUGGGCAUCGAACAAUCAAUCUAGGAGCGUGGCAGUGGGUAAAAUGGUGGACAGGCACCAAAGCUAUUUUCUCAUCUGUCCUGUGGAUGAGUGGAACUGUGGAACAAGUGAUGUGGAAUUAAUGGGUGCAACAGCUGUACAGACAAUCAAUAACACACACAGUUCUGGAAAGAACACAUCACUUGUGCUUGUUUGAUGAGCUUGUCACAUUCUAAUCCCUCUCCCCAUCCUGUUUCAAUUUUGGGAAACUUGUAUCUGCUGGUGUCAGCAAUUCUGAUUCUGAAAUAGGAUCAGGCUUUUACUACAACAGCCUUCUCUUUCUAUUUAUUGUGUCGACUCGUGGCUUAUGAAUAAAGGCAGGCAAAGUUUGCAGAACUGUCUUAAGGACAUUUAUUUUUUUUCCCUUUUUAAGUAAUUUUACACUUUAGUAUCUAUUUCAGAGUCAUAUUUAAAACUAUUUAUUAGUGACUACAGUACAUGAGACAACAAGGUUACUGAGAUUACAAUUCUUCAAAGGUUAAUGAUAAUGUGGUUUAUACUGUGCCUUAAUAGUAAUGCUAUUUAAGAUAUUUAUUUUUAAGUUUUACUAUGCUGCACUCUAAAGAAAGGAACUUUAGAUGUGACACUGUAAAAUUAUGUAUUCAUCUCAUGGCAUAAAUUAUUUAGUAAGUCUAGAUGUAGCGUAUUAAAUAUUAACCUAUUCAACUAAAGAUGUUGACUUGGAUUUAUUUAAAUUCAUAUGUGCACUGUAUAAGAGAGUACUCUUACAUUAACACAUUUUAGUUUAGUUUUUAGAUUUUUUUUUAAACGAUAUAUUGCUAGUUUCAUGCUUCCUCCUCUGAUUUUGCCUGUGUAGAUUUCAUUUAUUGGUAAUUCAUUAGUUUAACACUAUUAUGUAGUUUUUAAAUGCUGCUUUACAUUUUUCUUCUGAAACUGCAAUACUUGCAAUUUUUAUUCUUAAACUAAAUUGAAUACUAUUUUACACUGUAUUGGAUUUUUAUACUUGAACAAUUUCAUACAAGGGAAGACAGGUUAGCAUUUUUAUGGACUUUCUCCAUUAUCACUGGAUUUACUUUAAGUAUUCCCAUACUAGACAGUGUUAUGUAAUGUAGACAUGACUCUCCUGUGCAAAUUAUUUAUUCGUUGUGUAUAUUGCUUUAUAACAUUUCAGAUCUUCUAAUCUAUUCACUUGUAUUAAAUAUAAUUUUUAAAAA